AUUGGAGGCCCACGUAGGUGCAGAUUCCUCAUCUACAGGCGCUAGUGGACUGGAGACGGCUGGCGGCUGUCCCGGGACGGGGAAGAGAGCUUUGGUGCCUGAGGGAAGAUGGCUUAGGGCCCGGUCCCUUAAGGCCUCCCCACCUGCCCCCGCAAGGCGGCAUCUGCUGGUCCUGCUGCUGCUCCUCUCUACCCUGGUGAUCCCCUCCGCUGCAGCUCCUAUCCAUGAUGCUGACGCCCAAGAGAGCUCCUUGGGUCUCACAGGCCUCCAGAGCCUACUCCAAGGCUUCAGCCGACUUUUCCUGAAAGGUAACCUGCUUCGGGGCAUAGACAGCUUAUUCUCUGCCCCCAUGGACUUCCGGGGCCUCCCUGGGAACUACCACAAAGAGGAGAACCAGGAGCACCAGCUGGGGAACAACACCCUCUCCAGCCACCUCCAGAUCGACAAGAUGACCGACAACAAGACAGGAGAGGUGCUGAUCUCCGAGAAUGUGGUGGCAUCCAUUCAACCAGCGGAGGGGAGCUUCGAGGGUGAUUUGAAGGUACCCAGGAUGGAGGAGAAGGAGGCCCUGGUACCCAUCCAGAAGGCCACGGACAGCUUCCACACAGAACUCCAUCCCCGGGUGGCCUUCUGGAUCAUUAAGCUGCCACGGCGGAGGUCCCACCAGGAUGCCCUGGAGGGCGGCCACUGGCUCAGCGAGAAGCGACACCGCCUGCAGGCCAUCCGGGAUGGACUCCGCAAGGGGACCCACAAGGACGUCCUAGAAGAGGGGACCGAGAGCUCCUCCCACUCCAGGCUGUCCCCCCGAAAGACCCACUUACUGUACAUCCUCAGGCCCUCUCGGCAGCUGUAGGGGUGGGGACCGGGGAGCACCUGCCUGUAGCCCCCAUCAGACCCUGCCCCAAGCACCAUAUGGAAAUAAAGUUCUUUCUUACAUCUAA